AGAAAGUACUCAAGACAUUCACGGUGCCCCGGUCAGCACUCGCCAUGACGAAGACUUCUACAUGCAUAUACCACUUCCUUGUUCUGAGCUGGUAUACUUUCCUCAAUUAUUACAUCUCACAGGAAGGAAAAGACGAGGUGAAACCCAAAAUCUUGGCAAAUGGUGCAAGGUGGAAAUAUAUGACGCUGCUUAAUCUGCUCUUGCAGACCAUUUUCUACGGGGUCACCUGCCUGGAUGAUGUGCUGAAAAGAACCAAAGGGGGAAAAGACAUUAAGUUCCUAACUGCCUUCAGAGACCUGCUUUUCACCACUCUGGCUUUUCCUGUAUCCACGUUUGUAUUUUUGGCAUUCUGGAUCCUCUUUCUCUACAAUCGAGAUCUCAUUUACCCCAAGGUCCUAGAUACUGUCAUCCCCGUGUGGCUGAAUCAUGCAAUGCACACUUUCAUAUUCCCCAUCACAUUGGCUGAAGUCGUCCUCAGGCCUCACUCCUAUCCAUCAAAGAAGACAGGACUCACCUUGCUGGCUGCUGCCAGCAUUGCUUACAUCAGCCGAAGAUGAAAAGCACCUAAGGCCACUGCUGUUAUUGGGGAAAAUUGUAGUGGCUAUAAAAAUGAGUAGUAGAGGCCAGGAGGUUGGUUUGUCAGUACCUGGGCGGGUGUCCCCAUGAUGCAGGUAAUUAGGAUGUUGGAGAAAGAAAUGCCACAGGAUGGGAGCCAGGUACAAGUGCAUCGUUAUCCAUUCAGUGGUUCACCAGCGCCAGGCACUGUGCUAAAAUAUGGAGGAUACAGUGAAGUUCAGGAAACCUGCUACCUUUAGAGGCUGUCCGGGAAAGAGGAGCAUAACAGACAGUGGGAGACAGGGUGAUAGGACUGUAAUAGGCAUAAGCCCAGGAUGCUAUGGGCACACAGAGAGAUGUGCAGGACUGGCUUCUUAAAGGGAAGCACUGUCUAAGCUGAGGCCCAAGGAAUGAAUAAGAAUAGGUCAAAAGAGACAUGGAAAAGACCUUCAGGCAGAAAAAACAGCAUCUGCAAAGGGCUGGAGGAGCUGAGGGUAUGGCUGAAUUGGAGGACAGGGUAAAGCCAGGUCGUAAAUCCACAUUAGUGCGUUUGGACUUUUAAACCAAGUGCUUUUCUGUAGAAAAGUGUUAUAAUCAGAGGAAUGAAAUGAUGUGGUUUAUGUAAGAAAGCUGAUUAGAAAGAUGAUUCUGGCUGAAGUGUGGACAUUAGACUGAAGAGGAACAAGACAGGUAGACCAGUUGGUGGCAUUGCUGGUAACUCAGGGGAGUUGAUGUUAGCCAACUGAUGAUAACAUCAGUCAAUCCACAAAUAAAAUCAGAGAGUGUGAACAAUGGGAGGUGACUUAGAGAUGACUUAGCAUUGGAAAACUAAAUCUCCAGUAGGGUAGAUGACAUGCCCAUGGUCAUAUGGCAGAGGUGGGGUAGAGAUGCAAAGCUGGUACUUGAGCCAACUAAAACUGAGGUCUCCUCUCUCCAAAUCCAGUUGUCUUUCCACUGUGUUUACAUGGCCAGGUAUUUGUUCAAUUCCCAGUGUGUGCAAAACCAUUCAGCUAAAUGCUGGAUGGAUGGGCAUGCACAAAGCUUGACCUAGCUCUGCACUUUGAAAUCUUUCACGUGUUGUUCCCAGCUCUAUGUGCUUGGAUUAGACAUUAAAGUACUGGUAAUGAAGGGAGUGGAGGGAAGGGAUGGAGACCUGUCACCAGCAGGAACGUGACUGGGUGAGCCCCAGUGCCCAGUGGGGAGCUGAGGUGGUUUGGGAUUUCGUCCUUCAUGAAAAAUGCUAAGUUGGUAUUUGGUCCACUAAGCCCCAUUUUUGCUAGAACAAAUCAAAUAUAGACACUUAAAGGAGGGUGUUUGAUGUGAUCCUGUUGAUGGAAGCAUCUCUAUUUCUGCUCACGCCCUGGUUAGAGGAGCUCAGACUCUUUGGUGCCUGCCAACCCCACCCUUACGCAGUUUCCAGGGCCCCUGGCUCCUCACAGCCACAGAUGGCCAUGAAGUUCUACAAACUGCAGACACCCAUGGAGACGUUUUAGGGAAGUGGCUAUGGGCCCACUGUCAGAUGUGCCAGUUUGGACAGUCAAAUGGGGAAAUGGCAUAACACGAAUGAGGUAAAGAGCAUGGGCUCGGGCCAGAGGGAGCGUGAGAAACGAACAUGAGUCAGGAAAACGGCACUGAAGCUGAGCUGGAGAAGCAUUUCACCGCCGAAACCAUGUUCAAAUGACCUAAAAAUAGUUCCUGAGACCGUGGGGACCGCCUUACAUGUGGUGGUUGCUUUUAGUUAUUUUUCAGAUUGCAAAAUUGAAGAGCUCUCCCCUAAGUGGGAAAAUAAAGCUUUGCAAAAUAGUAAUGACUGCAAAGCUUUCAUUUCCUUUGGAAAGCAUUAGUCACCUUUAAAUAUGGUAGCUCACUUAUUUCUCCCUUCUCUCCUACCCCAAAACACCUCACCUAGUUCUCCCUGAGGCAGUGGUGAGGAGCAAAAAAAUAGAAAUGUUCCUUCUGCUGGUUUUUAUUCUUUCUUUUAUUGAAUAAAUAUUUUCCCUAACACAUGGUUGGUCCUGCCCAGAAAAGCAAUGUUAUAUCAGGCCAAGCUUCAGCCUGCAGGGGGUUUAUCCUUAAUAAGUGGAGAUGACCCAUGCAUACAAAUUAUAAGUGCAGAAGAUGGAAAGUGGUAAAACCUCAUAAAAAAAACACAAGGAGCCACAGAAAAGGAAGAGUUUGCAUCCAGCUGAGCGGUGUGGGAAGGGCACUGUGGAAGGCAUGCAUUGGAUCUGAGCCCUGAAGGACCGGCAGGAUUGGAGCUAGAAAAAAUGAGAGAAGGUAAACAAAAGGAGCACAGUCCCAAGGCCAGGAGAGUGCAGAAAGCGUGAGAGCAAGGGUCAGUAAUUCUCUUUGCUGGACCUGUUUGUGAAAGAGACUAAUGAGAAAUAUCCCUGGAACUACCCACUCAUGAAGGCUUGCAGAUGGCAGACUAGAGGAUGUUGGACAUAGUAUAGAAAAUGGGAGCAUUUGUUGUUGCUGUUGUUUGUUUGUUUGUUUGGAGUGGAAGCAAGGGUGAGCAGUAUUUGUAACUUGGCCAGCAAAUUAUGCUUUAAAAUGUCAUUCUUGACAAUAGUGCUUCAAAUAAGUUGGAGUGACAAGAGAUGGGAAACAAAAUAAAAUAUAAACCAAUAUAAAAAUAAAAACUAGCCAGCACAUUAUGUACUUUGAUCACAA